AGUGCAACUGAAACUUUUGUAUUAGCAUACUACUGAGAAUAUCUAACAUGUUGUUACUAAUCAAUGUCAUUCUGACCUUGUGGGUUUCCUGUGCUAAUGGACAAGUGAAACCUUGUGAUUUUCCAGACAUUAAACAUGGAGGUCUAUUUCAUGAGAAUAUGCGUAGACCAUACUUUCCAGUAGCUGUAGGAAAAUAUUACUCCUAUUACUGUGAUGAACAUUUUGAGACUCCUUCAGGAAGUUACUGGGAUUACAUUCAUUGCACACAAAAUGGGUGGUCACCAGCAGUACCAUGUCUCAGAAAAUGUUAUUUUCCUUAUUUGGAAAAUGGAUAUAAUCAAAAUUAUGGAAGAAAGUUUGUACAGGGUAACUCUACAGAAGUUGCCUGCCAUCCUGGCUACGGUCUUCCAAAAGCGCAGACCACAGUUACAUGUACGGAGAAAGGCUGGUCUCCUACUCCCAGAUGCAUCCGUGUCAGAACAUGCUCAAAAUCAGAUAUAGAAAUUGAAAAUGGAUUCAUUUCCGAAUCUUCCUCUAUUUAUAUUUUAAAUAAAGAAAUACAAUAUAAAUGUAAACCAGGAUAUGCAACAGCAGAUGGAAAUUCUUCAGGAUCAAUUACAUGUUUGCAAAAUGGAUGGUCAGCACAACCAAUUUGCAUUAAUUCUUCAGAAAAGUGUGGGCCUCCUCCACCUAUUAGCAAUGGUGAUACCACCUCCUUUCUACUAAAAGUGUAUGUGCCACAGUCAAGAGUCGAGUACCAAUGCCAGCCCUACUAUGAACUUCAGGGUUCUAAUUAUGUAACAUGUAGUAAUGGAGAGUGGUCGGAACCACCAAGAUGCAUACAUCCAUGUAUAAUAACUGAAGAAAACAUGAAUAAAAAUAACAUAAAGUUAAAAGGAAGAAGUGACAGAAAAUAUUAUGCAAAAACAGGGGAUACCAUUGAAUUUAUGUGUAAAUUGGGAUAUAAUGCAAAUACAUCAAUUCUAUCAUUUCAAGCAGUGUGUCGGGAAGGGAUAGUGGAAUACCCCAGAUGCGAAUAAGGCAGCAUUGUUACCCUAAAUGUAUGUCCAACUUCCACUUUUCCACUUCUCACUCUUAUGGUCUCAAAGCUUGCAAAGAUAGCUUCUGAUAUUGUUGUAAUUUCUACUUUAUUUCAAAGAAAAUUAAUAUAAUAGUUUCAAUUUGCAACUUAAUAUAUUCUCAAAAAUAUAUUAAAACAAACUAAAUUAUUGCUUAUGCUUGUACUAAAAUAAUAAAAACUACUCUUAUAUUGGACUUCUUAUCAAUGAAUUAGUAAGUAUAGAGACAGACAGCUGAAUGGCUUUCUGCAUAUUGUAUAGUAUACCUAGACAUAGAAACAAAAUGACUUUAGAUUUUAUUUGGGGAAGUAAUAAUACCAUAAAAUUAGAUAUUAAAAUUGUAAGUGAAGAUAAACACACUAUAGUAUUCCCUUAUUGUAGCCAUGGUCCUCUAGAUGCAGUUAACCAAAUAGGGUCAUUUUUAUUAAAAGUAGUGUUUCCUGGCAAACACUGACAUUACAUCAUUAUCAUGAUUUAAAGGAAAUAGUACUAGAGAAGGUGAAUUAUUAUCAUUUUCCUGUGAAAAAAGAAAAGAGGUUUUGCUAACCCUUUCAGAGCAUUGGGAACACAGCCAGAAGUGCAUUAAAUGUAUAUAUUAACUUGGGCAAUGUUGACACUUUAGGAUGCUGAAGCCAGGUGCAGUGGCACACGCCUGUAAUCCUAGCACUUUGAGAGGCCAAGCUGGCAAUCAUCAGAGGUCAAAAGUUCAAGACCAGCCUGUUCAACACGGUGAAACCCUGUCUCUACUAAAAAUAGAAAAACUAGCUCGGCAUGAUGGCGUGCACCUGUAGUCCCAGCUACUCAGGAGGCUGAGGUGGGAGAAUCACUUUAACCAGUGGGGCAGAGGUUGAACUGAGCCAAGAUAGUGCCACUGCACUCCAGCCUGGGCAAUAGAGUGAGACUCUGUCUUAAAAAUAAAUAAAUAGGAUGCUGAAAAUUCCUAUUUAAGGAAAUAAUUCUUUUUCUGAUUUAUUUAAGGCUACAUUUGUAUUUUCUUAAUACAAAUAUUUUGAAAGUUUCUUCAUAUAUGGUUUUUUGCAUUUCUUAUUAAGUUUUGCUUCAGAUUUUUUUUUGUCUUUUCUCCUGUUAAUUGCCUUCACUCUCUUUCUGUUCUGUACUUUUCUUUGUAUAUAAGGAUUUUUUGAAAAGAUUGUAUAUCCCUGUUAACAAAUUGAAAUCUCUAUUCACUUUAAUAGAUUUUUACCCCCAGUUAGCAUAUGGUUAGUGAGAAGUUGCAGGGUAAGAAGAAAACAAUGUUCCCUUUCCCAACACUUUUCCUGAUUAUAGAGAAAAAAGCAUGAACUUGUAUAAUGAUCUAGUCCUGUACAGAAUGAGAAAUAUUAAUUGCUAGACUGAGAAUGUUUUGGUGGCUAAAGCUAGGAAUAACUUUUUAAGACUGAAGAAUGAUAUAAGCUAUCAAAUCUAACUCAGUUUUCAAAUAACAGGUUUGCAGAGACUGGAGAAUAAAAAGUAAAAAAUUGUUUUAUUAAUUCCAGUGACUAAUUCUACUUCAUCAACAUACAUCAUAAAUAAAAUUUCAAAAAUAAUUGCUGAUAUGGUUUGGCUGUGUCCCACCCAAUUUUCACCUUGAAUUAUAUAAUCACCAUGCAUCAAAGGUAGGGCCAGGUGGAGAUAAUGGAAUCAUGGGAGCAGUUUCCCCAUACCCCACUCAUGGUAGUAAAUACAUCUCAUGAGAUCUAAUGGUUUUAUAAAUGAAAGUUCCCCUGGACAAGUUCUCUUGCCUGCCACCAUGUAAGAUGUACCUUUGCUACUCAUUCACCUUCUGUCAUGAUGGUGAGGCCUUCCCAGCAAUGUGGAACUGUGAGUCCAUUAAACCUCUUUCCUUUAUAAAUUA